AGACAGAGGGGCCAGGCUGAAGCUGGAGAGGAACCAGCGUCACACAGACGGCCUCUGAGAACUUGGAGACCCCGUUACCCACCCAGCAGGGGUGUCAGGACAAGCAUCUGCUGCAGGCUUCAGCCUCAGGGGCAAAAGGGAGCCCCGGGGUCCUGGUGGGGGCACCGACCACAGGCCCGGAGGGUGGAUGCCUGCAGGAAGCUGGGCUCUGUGGAGCCCGAGGAGGGGCUGGUGGCCACACCCCCCGGCCCCCUGGCUCGGCGGCCCUCAUGCCCGCCCUACGUCCACUCCUGCCGCUCCUGCUCCUCCUCCGGCUGACCUCGGGGGCUGGCUUGCUGCCAGGGCUGGGGAGCCACCCGGGCGUGUGCCCCAACCAGCUCAGCCCCAACCUGUGGGUGGACGCCCAGAGCACCUGUGAGCGCGAGUGUAGCAGGGACCAGGACUGUGCGGCUGCUGAGAAGUGCUGCAUCAACGUGUGUGGACUGCACAGCUGCGUGGCAGCACGCUUCCCCGGCAGCCCAGCUGCGCCGACGACAGCGGCCUCCUGCGAGGGCUUUGUGUGCCCACAGCAGGGCUCGGACUGCGACAUCUGGGACGGGCAGCCCGUGUGCCGCUGCCGCGACCGCUGUGAGAAGGAGCCCAGCUUCACCUGCGCCUCGGACGGCCUCACCUACUACAACCGCUGCUAUAUGGACGCCGAGGCCUGCCUGCGGGGCCUGCACCUCCACAUCGUGCCCUGCAAGCACGUGCUCAGCUGGCCGCCCAGCAGCCCGGGGCCGCCGGAGACCACUGCCCGCCCCACACCUGGGGCCGCGCCCGUGCCUCCUGCCCUGUACAGCAGCCCCUCCCCACAGGCGGUGCAGGUUGGGGGUACGGCCAGCCUCCACUGCGACGUCAGCGGCCGCCCGCCGCCUGCUGUGACCUGGGAGAAGCAGAGUCACCAGCGAGAGAACCUGAUCAUGCGCCCUGAUCAGAUGUAUGGCAACGUGGUGGUCACCAGCAUCGGGCAGCUGGUGCUCUACAACGCGCGGCCCGAAGACGCCGGCCUGUACACCUGCACCGCGCGCAACGCUGCUGGGCUGCUGCGGGCUGACUUCCCACUCUCUGUGGUCCAGCGAGAGCCGGCCAGGGACGCAGCCCCCAGCAUCCCAGCCCCGGCCGAGUGCCUGCCGGAUGUGCAGGCCUGCACGGGCCCCACUUCCCCACACCUUGUCCUCUGGCACUACGACCCGCAGCGGGGCGGCUGCAUGACCUUCCCGGCCCGUGGCUGUGAUGGGGCGGCCCGCGGCUUUGAGACCUACGAGGCAUGCCAGCAGGCCUGUGCCCGCGGCCCCGGCGACGCCUGCGUGCUGCCUGCCGUGCAGGGCCCCUGCCGGGGCUGGGAGCCGCGCUGGGCCUACAGCCCGCUGCUGCAGCAGUGCCAUCCCUUCGUGUACGGUGGCUGCGAGGGCAACGGCAACAACUUCCACAGCCGCGAGAGCUGCGAGGAUGCCUGCCCCGUGCCGCGCACACCGCCCUGCCGCGCCUGCCGCCUCCGGAGCAAGCUGGCGCUGAGCCUGUGCCGCAGCGACUUCGCCAUCGUGGGGCGGCUCACGGAGGUGCUGGAGGAGCCCGAGGCCGCCGGCGGCAUCGCCCGCGUGGCGCUCGAGGACGUGCUCAAGGAUGACAAGAUGGGCCUCAAGUUCUUGGGCACCAAGUACCUGGAGGUGACGCUGAGUGGCAUGGACUGGGCCUGCCCCUGCCCCAACAUGACGGCGGGCGACGGGCCGCUGGUCAUCAUGGGUGAGGUGCGCGAUGGCGUGGCCGUGCUGGACGCCGGCAGCUACGUCCGCGCCGCCAGCGAGAAGCGCGUCAAGAAGAUCUUGGAGCUGCUGGAGAAGCAGGCCUGCGAGCUGCUCAACCGCUUCCAGGACUAGCCCCCGCAGGGGCCUGCGCCACCCCGUCCUGGUGAAUAAACGCACUCCCUGUGCCUCAGA